GAAGGGCGCUUGGACCCCAGCGGCGAUCUGUGUUUGGGUUCGCGCUCUGGGAGAAUUUUGGCUUUGCUCGCCUUCCUCUUUCAGAAGACUCGAAAUCGGCCAGCAGGUCUGCGAGAUUUGAAACGCGACUGUUACUCCUUGUUUUCCGGUUCUGGCCGCGGGAGCCUCUCGAGAAGCGUGGAAAGAGGAGAAGGGCGUAUACCUUGUGACCGCCUCUGGUUGUCUUGGGCUCGCGCCUGGCGCCGCUACGUGGAGUCGCUCUCUCGUCGUCACUUUUGGCUGCCGACUUGUUGAGUAGAAGUGCAGACUGAUGCUUUAAGACUCAGGGAGAGGUCUUUCCCUUAUCUCCACCCCAGCAAGCACCCCAGAGACCUUGGAGAUUUGUCUUGUUUCUAGACACGUGUACUCCAAUGUUGUGCGGAGGAGGCCUUAAAUAUUCGAGAAGAGAGUGGGAACUCCUGGAAUUUUAAGGGAUUUCUGUGUAUUUCCAAAACUGACUUUUAACUACCGGCAGCGUGGGAUUUCGUGAUUGUUUUUCGCCAUCGUGUGGCUCCAACAUGUACUUCCCUUCUUGGUUAAGUCAGCUGUACAGGGGUUUAUCCAGACCCAUCAGAAGGACCACCCAACCGAUCUGGGGUUCUCUCUACAGAAGUCUGUUGCAGAGUUCACAGAGGAGAAUUCCAGAAUUCAGUAGCUUUGUUGUCCGGACCAACACAUGUGGAGAGUUGCGUUCGUCUCACUUAGGCCAAGAAGUCACCUUGUGUGGAUGGAUUCAGUACCGAAGGCAAAACACAUUCUUGGUCCUAAGAGAUUUCGAUGGGCUUGUUCAAGUUAUCAUUCCCCAGGAUGAGUCGGCAGCCUCUGUGAAGAAGAUUUUAUGUGAAGCCCCUGUGGAAUCUGUGGUGCAAGUGUCUGGUACAGUCAUUUCCCGUCCUGCAGGACAAGAGAAUCCAAAAAUGCCAACAGGUGAGAUUGAAAUCAAAGUUAAAACAGCUGAGCUUCUGAAUGCCUGCAAGAAGCUGCCCUUUGAAAUUAAGAACUUCGUGAAGAAAACAGAGGCUCUUCGGUUGCAGUAUCGCUACUUAGACUUGCGUAGUUUCCAAAUGCAGUAUAACCUGCGACUGAGGUCCCAGAUGGUCAUGAAAAUGCGGGAAUAUCUCUGUAAUCUGCAUGGGUUUGUGGAUAUAGAAACCCCCACAUUGUUUAAGAGGACCCCAGGGGGUGCCAAAGAGUUUUUAGUACCAUCCAGGGAACCUGGAAAGUUUUAUUCUCUCCCUCAGAGUCCUCAACAGUUUAAGCAACUUCUGAUGGUUGGCGGUUUAGACAGAUAUUUUCAGGUUGCCCGAUGUUAUCGAGAUGAAGGUUCAAGACCAGACAGACAGCCUGAGUUUACUCAGAUUGACAUAGAGAUGUCAUUUGUAGACCAGACUGGGAUCCAGAGUUUAAUUGAGGGUUUGCUCCAGUAUUCCUGGCCCAAUGACAAAGAUCCUGUGGUUGUUCCUUUUCCUACUAUGACUUUUGCUGAGGUGCUGGCCACCUAUGGAACUGAUAAACCUGACACUCGCUUUGGAAUGAAGAUUAUAGAUAUCAGUGAUGUGUUUAGAAACACAGAGAUUGGAUUUCUUCAAGAUGCACUUAGUAAGCCCCAUGGAACUGUGAAAGCCAUAUGUAUCCCUGAAGGAGCAAAAUACUUAAAAAGGAAAGACAUUGAAUCCAUUAGAAACUUUGCAGCUGACCAUUUUAAUCAGGAAAUCUUACCUGUAUUCCUUAACGCCAAUAGAAACUGGAAUUCUCCAGUUGCUAAUUUCAUAAUGGAGUCACAAAGACUGGAAUUAAUCAGACUAAUGGAGACCCAAGAGGAAGAUGUGGUCCUACUAACUGCUGGAGAGCACAAUAAAGCAUGCUCUUUGUUAGGAAAAUUACGACUGGAAUGUGCUGACCUUCUAGAAACAAGAGGAGUGGUGCUCCGUGACCCCACUCUGUUCUCUUUCCUUUGGGUGGUAGAUUUCCCACUCUUCCUGCCCAAGGAGGAAAAUCCCAGAGAGCUGGAAUCGGCCCACCACCCAUUUACUGCUCCCCACCCCAGUGACAUACAUCUCCUGUACACUGAGCCCAAAAAGGCCCGUAGCCAACACUAUGACUUGGUUUUAAAUGGCAAUGAAAUAGGAGGUGGUUCAAUUCGAAUUCACAAUGCAGAGCUGCAGCGUUAUAUCCUGGCAACCUUACUAAAGGAGGAUGUGAAAAUGCUCUCCCAUCUGCUCCAGGCUUUAGAUUAUGGGGCACCCCCUCAUGGAGGAAUUGCCUUAGGGUUAGACAGACUGAUAUGCCUUGUCACUGGAUCUCCAAGCAUCAGAGAUGUCAUAGCCUUCCCAAAGUCCUUCCGGGGACAUGACCUCAUGAGCAAUACCCCAGAUUCUGUCCCUCCUGAGGAACUGAAGCCCUAUCAUAUCCGAGUCUCCAAGCCAACAGACUCCAAAGCAGAAAGAGCUCAUUGAAUCAUGCAUACCAUGCAGAAAGUUGAGCUUUUAGGUUUUGUCCUCUUUGCUUCCCCAAGGCUAAAGUCAGAUCUAGAGUUCUGCCACAGGUCUAACAAUCAAGUCUUUAGAUGGAAGGAAUCCAGGCAACAUUCUUCACCACAACGAAGAAACAGAUAAAAGAUACCCAAUUUUGACUUGAUUUCAUGCAUCAUUUGGAUUUUUUUUGGUUAGGACUUUUUUUGAAGUUCCUUUUUACUUAGGUGUGAAAGAUGGUUCUUUGUUGAAAUAAUAUAGUGGUUUAGUGUUUUCAAAUCAUGUUUCUCAUACCCAGAUAGUAGAUUAUUCACUUAGGACAGAGGUAAUCAAAUUAUGUGUGAAAUGUAGGAAAAUGCUUGCCCCUGUAAACUAGUGAGUUGAUGGAGCAUUUGCUUCAUCAUCCUCAUCAAGAGAAUCAUAUAAAUUAAGCUUUAUAAUGACAUUUCAACCAUCAACAUAAUAUAGUGAGGAGUAGCAUAAUAUUUUUUAAUAAUGCAGAAAACAUCACUGAAAUGAGAGUCACAAAUUUUUCUUCAGUGUUUCAGCCUGAGUAAGUUACAUAAACCUCGCUUAGCCUCCCUUCCUGCUAAUGUGUAAAAUACAUACUUGCCCUGGCUACCUCACCGGGCUGUUAUUGCUGGAAUCAGAGGAGAUAACAUAUAUGGAAGAUAAAGUGAAUAAAAGUACUUUGAAAAACUAUAAAGCAUUCCACAAAUAUGAGAUGAUGGUAUUAUCCAUCCAUAAAUAGGUAGAUAUAUCUCUAUUUUAUAGUUUCAGAUUAAACAAAACUGAUAUCAAUAGUAAAAGUCAUUUUACUUAUCAA